AGGCUGUGGCAGCGACGCGGUCCCCAGCCUGGGUAAAGAUGGCCCCAUGGCCCCCGAAGGGCCUAGUCCCAGCUAUGCUCUGGGGCCUCAGCCUCUUCCUCAACCUCCCAGGACCUAUCUGGCUCCAGCCCUCUCCACCUCCCCAGUCUUCUCCCCCGCCUCAGCCCCAUCCGUGUCAUACCUGCCGGGGACUGGUUGACAGCUUUAACAAGGGCCUGGAGAGAACCAUCCGGGACAACUUUGGAGGUGGAAACACUGCCUGGGAGGAAGAGAAUUUGUCCAAAUACAAAGACAGUGAGACCCGCCUGGUAGAGGUGCUGGAGGGUGUGUGCAGCAAGUCAGACUUCGAGUGCCACCGCCUGCUGGAGCUGAGUGAGGAGCUGGUGGAGAGCUGGUGGUUUCACAAGCAGCAGGAGGCCCCGGACCUCUUCCAGUGGCUGUGCUCAGAUUCCCUGAAGCUCUGCUGCCCCGCAGGCACCUUCGGGCCCUCCUGCCUUCCCUGUCCUGGGGGAACAGAGAGGCCCUGCGGUGGCUACGGGCAGUGUGAAGGAGAAGGGACACGAGGGGGCAGCGGGCACUGUGACUGCCAAGCCGGCUACGGGGGUGAGGCCUGUGGCCAGUGUGGCCUUGGCUACUUUGAGGCAGAACGCAACGCCAGCCAUCUGGUAUGUUCGGCUUGUUUUGGCCCCUGUGCCCGAUGCUCAGGACCUGAGGAAUCAAACUGUUUGCAAUGCAAGAAGGGCUGGGCCCUGCAUCACCUCAAGUGUGUAGACAUUGAUGAGUGUGGCACAGAGGGAGCCAACUGUGGAGCUGACCAAUUCUGCGUGAACACUGAGGGCUCCUAUGAGUGCCGAGACUGUGCCAAGGCCUGCCUAGGCUGCAUGGGGGCAGGGCCAGGUCGCUGUAAGAAGUGUAGCCCUGGCUAUCAGCAGGUGGGCUCCAAGUGUCUCGAUGUGGAUGAGUGUGAGACAGAGGUGUGUCCGGGAGAGAACAAGCAGUGUGAAAACACCGAGGGCGGUUAUCGCUGCAUCUGUGCCGAGGGCUACAAGCAGAUGGAAGGCAUCUGUGUGAAGGAGCAGAUCCCAGGUUGGCUCUCAGCAGCCUUAUACCUUCCAGGGUACAAAGGGAAUCAGACCUGGCAUCAAAUCAGUCUGCCUCCUUAACCUGUUUCCUCAUCUAUCCAAUGGGACCAGUGUUUGCCCUGGCCUGCUGAGAGCUGUCCUAGGCCGGGGGUGUGGUGAGAUGCAGGGUAAUCACAACGAUGAUGGCAGGGACCAUUUCCCCAGCAAUUACUGUGUCAGAUGCUGUUCUAGGUGCAUUCCCCAUCUUAACUGAUUUAACCCCUGAAACAACCCGACGCUGGAAGUUGGGUUCUCAUCCCCACUCUACAUAUGUAAAAAUGAAGAUGCAGAGAGAUGAAGCUACUUUCCCAGGGCUAUAUGGCAAGCAAGUCGCAAAGCUGGGAUCCCAAUCCAGACAGUCUGACCGUGGAACGAGACUCAUACACGUAAUAAAUGCUCUGCCCCCAACUUGUCCACCACAUGGCCUUGGCAAGUCCAACCCCUUUACCUCUCUGAGCCUCACUUUCCCAUUUAGUGAGACAGGGAUGGUAACUGCCCCUUGCAGGGUGGUUUUGAGCAGUAAAUGUAGUGUGCCUGGCUUGCUGGGCAGGCCUGGUGGCCAUGAUGAUCAGGUGUGUGGGAGUUCUGGGGAGACUCCAAGAACUACCAGGAACAGGGAUACGAGUGCCAGGCUGCAUCUCUUGCUCCUCUGCAGAGUCAGCAGGCUUCUUCUCAGAGAUGACAGAAGACGAGUUGGUGGUGCUGCAGCAGAUGUUCUUUGGCAUCAUCAUCUGUGCACUGGCCACGCUGGCUGCUAAGGGCGACUUGGUGUUCACCGCCAUCUUCAUUGGGGCUGUGGCGGCCAUGACUGGCUACUGGUUGUCAGAGCGCAGUGACCGUGUGCUGGAGGGCUUCAUCAAGGGCAGAUAAUCGCGGCCACCACCUGUAGGACCUCCUCCCACCCACGCUGCCCCCAGAGCUUGGGCUGCCCUCCUGCUGGACACUCAGGACAGCUUGGUUUAUUUUUGAGAGUGGGGUAAGCACCCCUACCUGCCUUACAGAGCAGCCCAGGUACCCAGGCCCGGGCAGACAAGGCCCCUGGGGUAAAAAGUAGCCCUGAAGGUGGAUACCAUGAGCUCUUCACCUGGCGGGGACUGGCAGGCUUCACAAUGUGUGAAUUUCAAAAGUUUUUCCUUAAUGGUGGCUGCUAGAGCUUUGGCCCCUGCUUAGGAUUAGGUGGUCCUCACAGGGGUGGGGCCAUCACAGCUCCCUCCUGCCAGCUGCAUGCUGCCAGUUCCUGUUCUGUGUUCACCACAUCCCCACACCCCAUUGCCACUUAUUUAUUCAUCUCAGGAAAUAAAGAAAGGUCUUGGAAAGUUAAAAGGCAUCAGUCUUACUACCUGUCCCACCACCCCCACCUUAGGGAAAUGUCCUAGAAUCCUGGGAAAUUGAGGGCUUCUUUGAUGGUGAGUGGAGAAAAGAUAGAGGAGAAGGUUGCCCCUGAAGUGCUGUUAGGAGAAGGAGGAUAGAGGAAUCAGCCUUAGGAGGGUUCCAUGCCAGCUGUCAUUUGGCAAAGGACCCUGGACAGAUGACUUUUGCCUCUGAACUUCACUCUUCUCUUUCCUCAAAUGGGCUUCAUAAUGCUUUCCACUCAGGCUUAACAUGAGAAUUAAAUGAGGUGACAAAUGUGAAGACCUGGACAGUACACAACAGAUAUUCAAUAAAAGUGUGGUCGCCAUUAUGACCAGAGCCUCCAA